ACUCUUUGAGAUGUGUGGUGGUGGUGGUAGUGCUUGUGGUGGUAGUGAUAGUGGUGGUGAGGAGGGAGUUGCCCCUAUCUGCUUUAGAAGAUCCAAAGAUGUUAGUAAAUAGUUUUGGGGGAUCUUGAGGGUGUCUUGAGGGUCCAAGCCUGGGCCACUGCACAUUGGUGCUUCAACAGUAAGAUGGGCUUCAUGGGUUUGUGAAAAUGAAGAGAAAGAAAAGGGGGAGGGAAAAUAACAGUCUUUAAUAGACUGUGAGCAGUUCCUGGUAGAUUGCCACUAAUAAUAAUAUAAUAAUUUGCAUAAAGGGACUAAGUAGAAUUAAAUGAGCAAGGAAAGAGAAAGUUGGUGAGAAACAGCAUUUUCAAUCUCUAGUGUAUGUUUUAGAACGAACUUUUCAACAACCUGGGAUGUUUAGUGCAUGAAGUUCUCCUCCCUCCCCGCCAUGAAGAGUGGACGUUGGGAGGCAGUUUAAAACUUUUAUGAAUAUAACCCUCUUCUCCCAUUCAGAGAAGAAGAUAAUUAGUCACCAUAAUCUUCAAUGAUGAAGGGCUAAGGAUAUUUAAGUCUCCUUGAGCUAGGCUUUGUGAAAAGUUCUUUCUCAGGCCAGCCUUUGUGAAGCCUUCUCAGUUAGACCUUUCAGCACCCUCAUUUAGUAGCUAAGAAUAGUUUGAAAUGCCAUUUUGGAUGUGGUAUACAUUUUCAUCCAUCUCCCACCUAUCUUCAAUUGGACAAGUGCGUCAAGCCUGUAAGUGAUGGUGUUCAAAGACUUAUUACUGAGAUGUCCUUAACCCAUUGCUUAUUUGGGAACACAUUAUUAACAUACAUUUUAAAAUAACUUUGGUUGAUUUUAAUGAGUGAAAGGAAAGUAGGAAGGUAGAGAAGGGCGACAAUUUUAAAGGCUAUCCUGUUUCAGAUCAGCUGGGAGGGAAAAGCUGGCCUGACCAAACUACAUUUUAUAACUGGCCUGGGACAUUUUAACAGCCAGGUGGUUGUAGAGUAGUUGCCUCUAUUUACAGAUGAUAACUAAGGUUCCAACUAUUCUGUAUGGGUUUAUCCGGCGUCAUUGACAGACACUUUCUGGCACUACAUCAUACUUCAUUUUAAAUUACUUCUUUCCUUGGAAAAGUUCGUGGCUUUGUAAAAUUGUAAGUGCUUUUUCUACCUUCACAGUCUAGAUGUGAAGUAAACCUCUGACCACAAUUGUAUGUGGAGUCACUUUUACAUGAAAUUUGUGGAUCUGUUUACCUAUUUAAAAGAUUUUAGAAAGGGAAUUUUAAUAAUUCAUAGUCAAUGCAGUUUUGGAUUUGGAAAUUAAAAUUUCAUUUCUGGUUUAUGAAGUUUGAUUUAUUAGACUAAUUCCCAACAAGGACAUUUGUAGAGUUGCUUUUUCUUUCUGAGGUUUUGUAAAGACUGCAUCAGACUCUAGAAUGCUUUAAGAAUAGCCUAAUCAGAAGGCAGGGGGAUGGAUACUAUGACCUUGAGGUCCCAUUGAGUGCCAGAAUUCUAAGUGGGUACAUCUGCUUCUGUGCCUCUCCCAAGAGCCCUCUCCCAGGGCCUGCGCCUUCUUUAAAAGGGUGUCUUUGUAAUUAAGCGGCCCUUCUUCCCCAUCCCCCUUUCUUCCUUUGAUCCAGCUUUUUAAGGCCUUUUUUUCCAUUUGGAGACAAGAGGGGUUUCUCACACUUUCCUGUUCCCCUCUUAACGCUUCUUUUCCUUUACCCCAGAAAAGUCCCCUGAAGUUCUCAGGAUGGUUAGAAGUUGUUUUGUUUUGUUUGGGGCGUGGGGGUGGAGUGGGGGAGUUGUUACCAAUGAGGAGGAAUAGAGGAUAUAUUCCCUCUUGGGAAAUGCUUGUGACCAGGUAGCCUCCUCCAUGGAGACUGAGCAUUUGGAAUGCAUGAGAACAGUCUAUUCUUGGGGACUGUCUGGUAGAAAUUGUCCUUUGCACCCAUUAAGCCCAGCUUAAACACUGAAAGGGGUGGGGAGAGGUGUGUGUGGUCGUACUGGAGCCUUUUAGGAUGGUAAAUGGGUAAAUGUUUCCAAAUCUCCUAUUACAUCAUCUCUUUCUCCCAUGGAUUCAGUAGGUUUAGUGAUCUGCUUGACAAGUUAAUUAGCUGGGGACUAAACCAAUUUGUUUAGAAUUGUGAUCCAUUGAUUUCCUGUCCCCAGGAAUUUUUGUUGGUGUUUUACUAUGAUGUGUUGUCUUUAGUCUUACUUACUUUUCCCUCCUUGCUGCCUUUUGUGGACUUUGGUCCAAAUUCUAGGGUUCCACCCCCAAGUCAAAGGUUAGAAUUUUGUCCCAGGAACUAAGGGGGUAUUAAACAGGCUGGCCAUACUGCAUUACUCUCCUCCAUGGUGGGCUUCUGACCCCUUUUAACCCAGAGAAAGGAGGGAAGUCGCCCCUUCCACACACAACACACACAAUCUGAACAAAAAAAAAGAAAAAGAAAAAGAAAGAAAGAAAAUAGGAGGUCAUUUGCUUUAUAAAAGAAUCCACAACAGGUUUUCUUUGUAAGUACUAGCUUUCCUAGUUAGUGCCUUUAAACUAUGACUUGAUAUAUAAAAAUUCACUCUAACUGGGCCUUCUCGGAAGCAUAUUUAUUGCAUAAAGGAAUACAUAAGAAUUUGUAAUGAUUAUCGCUUAAAUUAAGUGAGGCCAUUAUUUGGCCUUUGAAAUCUUUUUGUUAUAUGGAAUGGAGUUAGUUAAUUGUCUAAAUCAUUCUGGCUUGUAAUAAUGCUGGCCACGUUAGCUCUGGCCUACAACUGCUUGCAGAAGAAAGCUAGUAUUACUUUUUGAAAAUAAAUCAGACUUUAUAGAUUUUGAACAAUUCUAAGGAUGAGACUAUCCACCCCAUAUAGGUAAAAUGUUUUAUUUCCAGCUACUGUAUUUGACUAACCCAGGGAUCCAGAAAGUUAUUUCUAGUAAAUAAUGGCGACUGAUGCCACUUUAACCUAAGAAUCUGCAAUAAGAUUUCCUAGUGAGCCUAUUGGUGAGAAGGACCUGGGCUCUAGGCCCAACUGUAACUCGGUUUACUACCUCUGUUAAGUUUUUUUUUUUCCACUGUAAAUUAUGGGUUUGGACAGGGUAAUUUUGAGAGCCAGUUCUUAUACGUUUAUGGUUUUCUUUCUAGGCCUCAAUAUCUAGUAUGAAUGUGAAUGAUUGCUACUAGAAUGAAGUGCAACAGUUGUUAGAAAUUCAAUCAUCUAGUCAUCAUGUUAAAGAAAAAAAGAUCCUGUAAGGAUAUAUGAAUAUAGAUGCAUUAUGUUUUACAUUUUAACAACCCAAAAUUAAGAAGCUAAGACUCUGUCCAAAACUUCAAGAAUUCCAUCAUCCUAAGAGAUCACCUGCUUUCAUUUUUUCUAGUUCCUUUCAAGUCCUGGUUCCUGUACUAACAUGAGUUUUAGAUAAUUGGAGCCACAGAUAUAUACAAUGUUGCUUUUCAAUAAGAGCCCACCCAAGACUUAACUUUGUGAACCCAUGUGGAGGAACUAAGUCAGAAUCUGACCGAGGACACAUGAAGACUCCCAUAUAUUUUGUUUCUCAAAUGCCAGGAGAGGCUAAUGGAUAUAAUAAGUAAUCCCUAAACACUCUCUGUGAUUCAGGAGUUGUUCAUGUAUCUAGCAAGGCUGUUAAUUUAAUUCCUUUGACCUCCUGUUAUCCCUCCCCCAUUCUUGUUAACAACAACAACAACAAAACUAGGGUCCACUGUUUACUUUGUGUAAAUCAUUGGCAAUGAUUUUUAAGUCACUGUAUGGUGAAAUCCCAUCAAGUGAGUAUAAAUUUGAGUGGAAUAUGAAAUCUCCAGAAUGAGAAAGGAGAAGCAGGAAAGCACAAAUAUACUUGUUUUGUAGCAUGGAAAAUAAUAUGUUUAAAUUAGACUAAAAGAUAGCAAAGAAACUAAGGAUUUUAGACAGUUAAAUAAAAGACAAGAAGUGCAGCAGCAGAAUGGCCCACACAUAAUGGGUUCUUCAUCUGAGGUCUUCACCAUGUAGUCAAAUUUCAUAGUUCUUUAAUUUUCCUUUGAUAACAAAGGUGUGGUAUACAUGUGAUCUCUAAGAUUUGAUGGAUUAGCCAGGCAUGGUAGCUCACACCUGUAAUCCCAGCGAUUUGGGAGGCAGAGGCGGGCGGAUCACCUAAGGUCAGGAGUUCAAGACCAGCCUGACCAACAUGGUGAAACCCCUGUCUCUACUAAAAAUACAGAAUUACCUGGGUAUGGUGGCGCAUGCCUGUAAUCCCAGCUACUCAGGAAACUGAGGAAUAAAUUGCUUGAACCUGGGAGGCGGAGGUUGCAGUAAGCCAAGAUCACGCCAUUGCACUCCAGCCUGGGCAACAAGAGCAAAACUCCGUCUCAAAAAAAAAAAAAAAAGAUUUGAUGGAUUCAUUCCUGGAAACCAGUGGCUCAUCAUAAAUUAGAUUAAAUUUCUCUAACUGGAAUAGAAAGUGUGGUAUGGGUUUUUAGUAUUUAGAAAGUAGCAAAUGAGGAACAGGAACUUUUUUUUUUUUGUAAUAUAUGAUCCUGGAGAAAAUGCAAAUGGGUGUAUUUGCCAAUGUUUCCUAAGGCAAUUCUUGAAAAUCUACUCUUUUAAGUCUGUGGGCUUGCCUUGACAUUUGUAAAGGCACUUUCACUCUUGCCCUAACUCCAUGAAAUAUCAUUAGCCUGUGUGACUUGAAGCCAGGAUCUGGUUUUCUCUGCCCAGCCCCUCUCUGUCUUACCAUGUGACCAAGGGUAAAUGAAUUAGCUGCUCUAAGCUUCAGUUACCCUUCUGGGAAGCAAGGAUAUUAAUAAUCACAGAGGUGUUUCGGCAUGCUUCAUAUUGGGCACAUGCUUUGAGGUCAUUGGAUGAAAGGUGUUUGCAUGAUGGCAGAGCAGGCUUAUUAUAGGGUCUUGAGCAGGUGUUCCUUUUUAAUGAGCUUUGCUCUCUUAUAACAUACAGUGCCCUUUGGUGCCCCAUUGCCUUACUGACUGUAAUUACCAUUAACCCAACAUUUGUAUUAUUGGCCCUCUCGGCUUUUUGGAAAAAAAAUUAAACAGUUUUGUACUGUGUGGUAAGUUGAGGUACAAAUAAGAGGACUCUAGCAUCUUACAGGGUGGUGAAAAAUAGCUUCAAAAAGAAACGUUAGUUGAAAAGGGCUAUAGAGAUCAGUGAGUUAUUCAAAGCUCCUCCAAAAGAUGAAAAAGAAUAAAGCAAACUUCUGUGUGUGUGCGCAUGCACGUUUUAAGGGAGAAAGUUUUCAGUAAUAUUUGCUUGUGACACAUACUGAUGAUAGCCAGUAACUGAAACCCAGCCAUUGUAGUGUUUUAUACACAGCUGGAUUUUAUUAAUGAUGGAAUAUUUAUGCUUGCUGUACAAUUCGUGGCUCAUUUCCAUGUGUAUGUCAGAACUUAAAUACCCCCAAAAGAAACAUUAAGAUAACAUGAAAUAUAAAUGUGGCCAAGCUAGAAAGGGUGGAUUUGGUGGAGAGUCUCCCUUCUUCUUAUUGGUGUCACAUCAGAUCACAAUAACUGUGCCGCCCCCCUAUCAACCUUAGGCAUUGAUACUGAUCUUUUUUUCCCCUUAUAUAUACCCCAUAGCAAACUUCACAUUUCAAUCUUUUUGAUAUGGACAAACGAUCUGCUCUCCUCUUUAUAAUGCAGAUAAAACUGAUGUAUGUGUUUUUUAAGAGCAUAUUUUCCCUGCACAUGCUUCUCAUUAUCCGAGAGGCCUGGACUCAAUCAGUAAAGGAGCAGAGAAACCACAUAAUUGAAAGGAGAAUGACGGUGGUGCAUACUUGGAAUAUUUGUGGGAAGGGGAUUGCUGACAUCAGAAAAUGUAGUGGCCUGAGUGUUAACAGCAUUGAAGAGAAAUCAGCUUUCUGUGUUUCUGUGUAUUGAAAAUUAUUUUUAAGGGAAUAAAAAUAUGGGCCAGGUUUGACAUCCUUUUAUGAAGUUGCCCUGGAAACUUUGAUGAAGAUUGUUAAAGAAUAGCUCAAUUAAAACCUUCCCCAUUAGGAAGCUAAUUAGUACAUCCCUUACUCAUUUUGGUUGUUUUCAAGGGGCAUGUAUUUGCAUUGAAUUAGUGACAUUUGUUCCAUGUGAUAGCAAACUAAGAUAAAAAUCACAGAUGGGGAAAAUUAUUUAGAUUGCCUGUUUUGAAGAAACCUAAUUCCUCUUUAUUACAUUUAGAUUUUCAGUUCAGAGUUUUGUUUUACUAUGUUUAUAUACAAUGAUCACAUUUUAGUGUGGUAGCCAGUUUUGCUUUCUGGAUCAUGGGCUAUAAACCAAAGCUUAUUUGAAUUUCCCGUAUGAAUUAGGGAAAUAGAACAAAUGACAACAAACCAUUUUAUUAAGAGCUGCUAAGAAGGACAAAUAAGAUAGCAGAGUGAAAGAGCUUUUGUCUCCUUAGAAGGAAGGCUGAGAAACUAAAGAGUGACCAGUGGUUGGACUCUUGGCGGCGCUUACCCUGAACCUGAGUGUUAGGGGAGAGGGAAUCUGCCGUUGCGGUUUCUGGAGCUGCUCAUAAGCAAGAAUUCCCUAUCCUGAUCAAGGCUUUAAGCCUAAAAGAAAGCAGAAAUAGGUCAAGGGCAGCCCAGGUGCCCAAUUUCUCUCUCUCUUCACAAGGCACCACCAGCAAUAGAGAUGAGAAAUUCUGAAGAACAGCCAAGUGGAGGGACCACGGUAUUGCAGCGUUUGCUACAAGAGCAGCUUCGCUAUGGCAAUCCUAGUGAGAAUCGCAGCCUGCUUGCCAUACACCAGCAAGCCACAGGGAAUGGCCCUCCUUUCCCCAGUGGCAGUGGGAACCCGGGCCCUCAGAGUGAUGUGUUGAGUCCCCAAGACCACCACCAACAGCUUGUGGCUCAUGCUGCUCGACAAGAACCCCAGGGGCAGGAAAUCCAGUCAGAAAACCUCAUCAUGGAGAAGCAGCUGUCUCCUCGAAUGCAAAAUAAUGAAGAACUCCCGACCUAUGAAGAAGCCAAGGUCCAGUCCCAGUACUUUCGGGGCCAACAGCAUGCCAGUGUUGGAGCUGCCUUCUAUGUCACUGGAGUCACCAACCAGAAGAUGAGGACUGAGGGACGCCCAUCAGUUCAGCGGCUCAAUCCUGGAAAGAUGCACCAAGAUGAGGGACUCAGAGACCUUAAGCAAGGGCAUGUCCGUUCCUUGAGUGAACGACUAAUGCAGAUGUCACUGGCCACCAGUGGAGUUAAGGCCCAUCCACCUGUUACCAGUGCUCCCCUCUCCCCACCACAACCCAAUGACCUCUACAAGAAUCCCACAAGUUCCAGUGAAUUCUACAAGGCCCAAGGGCCACUUCCUAACCAGCAUAGCCUGAAGGGCAUGGAACACCGAGGCCCCCCACCAGAAUAUCCCUUCAAGGGCAUGCCACCCCAAUCUGUAGUGUGCAAGCCCCAAGAGCCAGGGCACUUCUAUAGUGAGCAUCGCCUGAACCAGCCAGGGAGAACAGAGGGGCAACUGAUGAGGUAUCAGCAUCCCCCUGAGUAUGGAGCAGCCAGGCCAGCGCAGGACAUCUCAUUGCCAUUGUCAGCCAGGAACUCGCAGCCUCACAGCCCUACUUCUUCUCUGACCUCUGGGGGGUCCUUGCCCUUGCUACAAUCUCCACCAUCCACUAGAUUGUCUCCUGCCCGACACCCCUUGGUCCCAAACCAGGGAGACCAUUCAGCUCACCUGCCUAGGCCGCAGCAGCAUUUCCUUCCUAAUCAGGCUCACCAGGGGGAUCAUUACCGUCUCUCCCAACCUGGCCUGAGUCAGCAGCAGCAGCAACAGCAGCAGCAGCACCAUCAUCACCAUCACCACCAACAACAGCAGCAGCAGCAGCCACAGCAGCAGCCAGGAGAAGCCUAUUCAGCUAUGCCUCGGGCUCAGCCAUCCUCUGCUUCUUAUCAGCCAGUGCCAGCAGACCCUUUUGCCAUUGUUUCCAGAGCCCAGCAGAUGGUUGAGAUCCUCUCAGACGAGAACCGGAACUUGAGGCAAGAGUUGGAAGGAUGCUAUGAGAAGGUGGCAAGACUGCAGAAGGUGGAGACAGAAAUCCAGCGCGUCUCGGAGGCAUAUGAGAACCUCGUGAAGUCAUCCUCCAAAAGAGAGGCCCUAGAGAAAGCCAUGAGAAACAAGCUAGAGGGCGAGAUUCGGAGGAUGCAUGAUUUCAACAGGGAUCUGAGAGAGCGUCUAGAGACUGCCAACAAGCAGCUUGCAGAGAAGGAAUAUGAGGGGUCAGAGGACACCAGAAAAACCAUCUCGCAGCUCUUUGCAAAAAAUAAAGAAAGCCAGCGUGAGAAGGAGAAGCUGGAAGCGGAGCUGGCCACUGCCCGUUCUACCAAUGAGGACCAAAGACGACACAUCGAAAUCCGAGAUCAGGCCCUGAGUAAUGCCCAGGCCAAGGUGGUAAAGCUGGAAGAAGAGCUGAAAAAGAAGCAAGUGUACGUUGACAAGGUGGAGAAGAUGCAGCAGGCCCUUGUACAGCUCCAGGCAGCAUGUGAAAAACGUGAGCAGCUAGAGCACCGUCUCCGGACACGACUGGAGAGGGAACUGGAAUCCCUGAGAAUCCAGCAGCGUCAGGGCAACUGUCAGCCCACCAACGUUUCAGAAUACAAUGCUGCUGCACUGAUGGAGCUCCUUCGGGAGAAAGAGGAGAGGAUUCUGGCUCUGGAAGCUGAUAUGACAAAGUGGGAGCAGAAAUAUUUGGAGGAGAAUGUGAUGAGACAUUUUGCUCUGGAUGCUGCUGCAACUGUGGCUGCUCAGAGGGACACAACAGUCAUCAGUCACUCUCCUAACACCAGCUAUGACACAGCUCUAGAAGCUCGCAUCCAGAAAGAGGAGGAAGAAAUCUUGAUGGCCAAUAAGCGUUGCCUUGACAUGGAGGGCAGGAUUAAGACCCUCCAUGCCCAGAUUAUUGAGAAGGAUGCCAUGAUCAAAGUACUCCAGCAGCGUUCCCGGAAGGAGCCGAGCAAGACAGAGCAGCUGUCGUGCAUGCGGCCAGCGAAGUCUCUGAUGUCCAUUUCCAAUGCUGGAUCAGGCUUGCUCUCCCACUCAUCCACCCUGACUGGCUCCCCCAUCAUGGAAGAAAAGCGAGACGACAAGAGCUGGAAGGGGAGCCUAGGCAUUCUCCUGGGUGGAGACUACCGUGCUGAAUAUGUCCCUUCCACACCCUCGCCUGUGCCACCCUCGACUCCCCUGCUCUCGGCUCACUCCAAGACAGGCAGCCGAGACUGCAGUACCCAAACUGAACGUGGGACGGAAUCGAACAAAACUGCAGCUGUUGCUCCCAUCUCUGUUCCUGCUCCAGUUGCUGCUGCCGCCACUGCUGCCGCCAUCACUGCCACUGCUGCCACCAUCACCACCACCAUGGUAGCUGCUGCUCCAGUUGCUGUUGCUGCUGCUGCUGCUCCAGCUGCUGCUGCUGCCCCGUCUCCAGCCACUGCCGCUGCUACUGCUGCUGCUGUUUCUCCAGCUGCUGCUGGUCAGAUUCCAGCUGCUGCCUCUGUUGCCUCAGCUGCUGCCGUUGCUCCUUCUGCUGCUGCUGCUGCUGCUGUUCAGGUUGCUCCAGCUGCUCCGGCUCCAGUUCCAGCUCCGGCUCUGGUUCCGGUUCCAGCUCCAGCAGCGGCUCAGGCUUCUGCUCCUGCUCAGACUCAGGCACCAACUUCAGCUCCGGCUGUGGCUCCAACUCCAGCUCCAACUCCAACUCCAGCUGUGGCUCAGGCUGAGGUUCCUGCAAGUCCAGCUACCGGUCCUGGACCACAUCGUUUGUCUAUACCAAGUUUGACCUGCAAUCCAGACAAAACAGAUGGGCCUGUGUUCCACUCCAAUACUCUGGAAAGAAAAACUCCCAUUCAGAUCCUGGGACAAGAGCCUGAUGCAGAGAUGGUGGAAUAUCUCAUCUAAACGGCCAAAUCAAGAGCUGCAGAUUAUCAGCAAAAAUGCUUUUAAUCAUUUUCCCCCUUUUAUUGGUUCUUGUUUUGAGGGUGAGGACAAGGGUUGUGGGGAGGGGAUGUUUUUUAACAGGACUUUUUAUUGGAACAAUGUACUACUUGAGUAAUACCAUGUGAACACCAGUCUAUUUUGGUAUGCUUAGGGAGUACCUCUAAAGACAGAUUAAUCAGAAUGUGCUCUAAAGCUUAUUGUUUGAAUUUAUACGAAUACUGGGACUGUUAACAGGUGGCUAUACAUCGACGUUUUCAAUGUGCUUAAAUUUGUUUAAAUUUUCCAUAUUCUAGAUCAUUUUUUAUUGAAGAGCACAGUAUGUGUGGAAGACAGUGUAUAACACGUAGUUUGGAAGUGGGAAGCUAGAGAGAAUUGAGUGUGUGCUGUUUUGUAUAGUUACUAUCCUGUGCAGCAGCUGGAGAAAGCACUCACCUCAGGCUUACAAAAGGGAAUAGUUUCAGGAGCUAUGUAAGCUGGAAAAAAGGUAGGGAGUUUUGGGGUGCAGAAGGGUACUGGAGCUAAUUUUUUCUUCCAGUUUCCCAGCUACCCUGCCCCAGGGAAUUGUGUUUGUCUUCAUUUCAGUGGUGCUUUGGAAAUGGAUUCUUUUGGUUCCCUCCUGGAGGUUCAUACAUUCAUAUAUAUGCUCUGGAGUAAUUUAUGCAUUUGGAUAAUUAAUAUAUUGCUUUCAGAUGCUGGGAGAGUACAUUAACUGAGUGAUGCGCAACUUCCUCUCUCUUAGGGAAUUAGACCAUCAGAGGCCUUGAUGGAGAGUUGCAUGGGGUGCUAUAUGCAGACUUCCAUGGUUUGUGUGUAGCCAUGAACACAGCUUGCUUGCAUUUAGUAAGACCAAUCAGCUUAGUGUUUAUUUCUUCUACAGCACAGAUUCACUGGCUGGGUCUCCAGUCUCAAAUUGCCAAUCAUUUGCAAAGUGAGGAAGGAUCUUUGUUGACAGGUUGAAUGCUUUGAAUUUCUGGUGACUACUUUGAAAUAACUUGUUUUGUUUGUCAAAUUCUAAGCAUAUGUCUUAAAAGGCAUUUUUGACUAUCACCUCCAAGGGAAUAGCUUGAGAAACCCAAAGUACUAUGCUGCAGUCGGGGGAGAGGUGGAUUGCAGCAGUAUCCUCAACUACCUCUUCUCACUGUCAGUGACACCAUCUUGGAAUACCUUUGGGAAGCAGCAGGAAAUGUGCAUGUGGGUAGAGAUCAAAGGAGGCAAUGGCUCCAAGCCUUGCCAUAGGGCUGCCUCCAAGGACACAGAAGGAUGCCAGUUGCCACAGGUCCCUGCCCUGUGUCACCUGUCUGCCCUUCAUUAAGGUGAGAAAUCUGCAGAUAGCAUCAUUAAGAUCAGUUUUAAGGGGUAUAGGGAGGGUGAGGGAAGUGGGGGGUGUUAGGUAAGGGUUGGGGGUAGAGGUUUUGGGAUGUCUUAGUUAGAAACCAGAUUAAUAGAAGAGUAGGCCUGAUAUAUUACAUCAUGAGCCAUAGUGGUGGGAAAGAACUUUAGCAAUAUAGCCCUACCUCCUCAUUUUAGUGAUGAGGAAUCUGAGAACUGGAGAGGUUCAGUGACUUUUUGAAAGUCAUACAACACAGCUAACCAUUAUGCCAAUCACCAUGCUUAUUUUGGGAAACUCUUUAUCUUUUUUAAAUUCCAUUUUAUGAAAAGGCAUCUUCAUGGUCCAGGGAAUAUGUAUCUUGUAAAAUGUACCUGGUUGGAGUAGCUUGUCCAGUCUUGACAAACUACUGAAUUUCUGUCUUGCCUCUCCUUCAGUGCCUUUUAAAAGGUUUUCCCUUUUCUGAUCUGCAUUUCAACAUAGAGUCACAUAAAUGUCCCCCUGAGAAACCAAUCCCACUUCUUUCUAGGAGAUUGGGUAUCUUAGAUAAUCUUUUGGGGUUCCUCUGUGAGUAUAGGAAUGGUAUCCUUCCUAAUUAUCUUCCAAAGGAAUUAUUUUGUGUGUGUGCCUGUGUGUGUGUAGAGACAUAAAGGAGGGUGAUGUGAUUUUCAGCUAGUCCUUUCACAUUUUCAAUAAUGAGGUAAUCAUGUUACAUACACAUUAGUCCUCAGUUAUAAAGUGAAUCUCAGAUAGAAAUUAAAAGUGCAGUUGUGUUAAGACUCUUUCAUACUACCCUUUAGUCAUAAGGAGAAAAAAACACUCAAAUAGUAGAAGCAGCAAGUAGCAAACUUCAGGAGAGCUACUUUCUAUCCAAAUAAUUUAAAAAACACUUUUCACCUACUCCUUUCAUGGUUAUAACACAUUGGCAGACUUUUUGCUGGCUCUGGGAGCCAUGAUUUUAAUCACAUUCUGCAAGGUGACAAAUGUCAUACAUUCCACAUUGUGUGGUAGCCAUCUCUUUAGACUCAUGUGUUUUGGGGAAAGGAAGAAGUUCUUGGCUGAGUACUAUUUUGAACUUUCCAGAACCCUCUCACACCAGAGACAGUUCUUCUCUGUUCAGUUUCCAAUCCCCGAUAAUUUGCUAAAAUAACAUUGUACAUCCAAGAGAGGGAAGAAGAGUAUGUCAGUAUAUUAUGCAGAAGAUAGAUACAGCCUUUUCAGAAGAUCUCCACUAGUUUUUGUUCCAAAAAUUCAAGUUUAUGGGAGAAAUCUCAAUUAGCCACCUUUUCACAGUUGUGUGGAUAUAACAUUUGGGGGAUCUUUCUGGACUCCUACCUAUCUGUGCAUUUUACCGGCACCUCAGGAAAGGAGGGUGACCAGGUUGUCUUAGCUUGUACUGCUUGGUGAUCUCUGAGGACCUUCUAAUUCAGUUGUACCCCAGUGUUCCAUGUAUAGAAAAACUUCAUUAGAACAAACUUUACUUGAUAUGAAACUCCUAUUAACAGUCUUUUUUUGAAAUAAAAAGUAGCUUGAGCUUUCUUUUAAAAUCAUGUAUCUUGAUUGUUGAUUUAAUGAAGGAUUUCCUUUUAAUGCUGCUUUUGAGCUUCAAGGUAAUAGGACAGCAGGAACCUAAAAUAUCUGCCAUCAUCUGCCAUAGGAAAGAUACCCAGAGACCCAUCAUGUUCUCUUUUUGUUGUUACACUGUUGGGUGGGUAUAACAAUUGGAAAAUGAACAAACUGAUUGAUUGUGCAAACUACUUUUUAUGACAAGCCUAAACCCUCAUAAUGCGGCAGCUUAAAGUGUAUACAUAUGCACUAACUUUGAUCAAUUAUAUUCUCAUAUCUGUUAGCUACACAGUCUCCUAUUAUCUCAAUUGCUUAUGUGCAUAUGGAAUAUGUUACUUAAAACGUGUGCAUUCUUACUGAAAAUGUUUUCAAAGGAAGGUAUCAGCUGUGGGCUAAUUGCCACCAAUUUCAGCCUGCCACGAUUCUUGGAAAUAUGUCUUCCAAGUGCCAUCCAUCAUCAGUAGGACAAGUGUCGGGAGUUUGUUUAUUUUUUUCCAGUAGCAACGAUGGGUUACAUGGAGCCAUGAAACCUCCUUCUGGCCUCCCUUGUGAUUAAUGGCAUGUGUUUGUAAAAUGGAUAGCUGGGGUUGGCAGAUGGCUAGAGAAGAAUCGCCUUUGGUUUAAAAUGUAUGUGGUCCCCUAAUGAUUGUGACCCCAUUCUGUAAUCAACUGAGCUAGUUCCAAUAAAGUUAAGCAGGUUUAAAUCCACUUUGUGCCUAUCUUUUCACUGACAAUAAAGUUAGCUAUUUUAAAAUGCA